AUUUCCGGGCACGGCUUCCGGCGUCCUUCCCUCUCAGGGAAGCUCCAGCUGUCCCUCCCGCAGUUGGCCCUGUGGUGUUCCGAAGCCGGUUACGUACGGCCUGAGGGCCAGGCGAACCUCAGGCUCUUUGUCCUACUAAAAAGCGCAGCACAAUGGUAGAAGCAGAUCAUCCUGGCAAGCUUUUCAUUGGUGGCCUCAAUAGAGAAACCAAUGAGAAGAUGCUUAAAGCAGUAUUUGGGAAACAUGGUCCCAUAUCAGAAGUUCUUUUGAUAAAGGAUCGAACCAGCAAAUCCAGAGGCUUUGCAUUUAUUACUUUUGAGAACCCUGCAGAUGCUAAGAAUGCUGCCAAAGAUAUGAAUGGAAAGUCUUUGCAUGGAAAAGCAAUAAAAGUAGAACAAGCCAAGAAACCAUCUUUUCAAAGUGGUGGUAGGCGGAGACCACCAGCUUCUUCGAGAAACAGAAGCCCUUCAGGAAGUCUGAGAUCUGCAAGAGGAAGCCGUGGAGGAACAAGAGGGUGGCUUCCCUCACAAGAAGGGCACCUGGAUGAUGGUGGAUACACUCCUGAUCUCAAGAUGAGUUAUUCUAGGGGACUCAUUCCAGUUAAAAGAGGUCCAUCUUCAAGAAGUGGAGGUCCUCCUCCGAAAAAAUCUGCUCCUUCUGCUGUGGCAAGAAGCAAUAGUUGGAUGGGAAGCCAAGGUCCCAUGUCACAAAGAAGAGAGAAUUAUGGAGUUCCUCCACGCAGAGCGACAAUAUCUUCCUGGAGAAAUGAUCGCAUGUCAACAAGACAUGAUGGUUAUGCAACUAACGAUGGAAAUCAUCCAAGUUGCCAAGAAACGAGGGAUUAUGCUCCACCAUCUAGAGGCUAUGCAUACCGUGAUAAUGGUCAUUCUAAUCGGGAUGAACAUUCCUCUAGAGGAUAUAGAAAUCAUCGAAGUUCCCGAGAAACUAGGGAUUAUGCUCCACCAUCUAGAGGCCAUGCAUACCGUGAUUAUGGUCAUUCUCGUCGGGAUGAAAGUUAUUCUAGAGGAUACAGAAAUCGUCGAAGUUCCCGAGAAACUAGGGAGUAUGCUCCACCAUCUAGAGGCCAUGGAUACCGUGAUUAUGGUCAUUCUCGUCGACAUGAAAGUUAUUCUAGAGGAUAUAGAAAUCAUCCAAGUUCCCGAGAAACCAGGGAUUAUGCUCCACCACAUAGAGACUAUGCAUACCGUGAUUAUGGUCAUUCUAGUUGGGAUGAACAUUCCUCUAGAGGAUAUAGUUAUCAUGAUGGCUACGGUGAGGCCCUUGGUAGAGAUCAUUCUGAACAUCUAAGUGGAAGUUCUUAUAGAGAUGCACUUCAGAGAUACGAGGAAUAGUACAGGUCAAAGGAAAUCAUUAGAUGUAUUGAUACUAAAGUUUAAGACAUCCGGAACAUUCUAUGUGAAGCAUUCUGUGACUGAAGAGGAUAACGGUAAUGAAAACUUUUUUUUUCACCUAAAUCAGAAGUGAACCAGCUAAGUUUCUCAGGUGCGUAGCAUAAUGAAUUUAAAUGUUCGUAGUUUAAAUAGUGGAAAGUAAGUGUUUUGUCUUGUGAGGUUCCCACGUUAAUUUUUUCUUGAAUAUUUUGACAGUGGAUGUUGUAAGUAAUGGUUUAGUAAUAUGUUCUUACAGAUAGGAAUAAUCUAGAGUGGUUGGGAUAGUAUCAGUUUUUUUUUGAGAUGAAGUGUAUAGCUUUGUCGCCGAAGCUGGGGUGCAGUGGCUCUGUCUUGGCUUAUGGCAACCGCUGCCUUCUGGAUCCAAGCUAUUCUCCUGCCUCAGCAUCCUGAGUAACUGGUAUUAGAUAUGUGUGCCGCACAGCGGGGCCAAUUUUUGUAUUUUUAGUGCAGACAGCGUUUCACCUUGUUUGCCAGGCUGUUCUUAAAAUCCUGAUCCACCCUCCUCAGACUCCCGAAGUGCUAAGAUUAUAGGCGUGUGCCACCACUGUCAGCCUAUCGUAUUUAAUUGAUAAUAUGAAUGGAAACGCUUUAAACCUCAUACUUAGGGGAAAGUGAAGUGUAUAAAACAUAAACAACAGCAUAAAGUUUCCGACGGGAUUGCUUAAAGUUUUAAGACAUCACUGAAUGAUACAAAUAUUUAGACCGAAAUAACUAAAUGAAUUAAUUUUCCUGAUUAUACAAACUAAAGAAAUGAAAUACAUCAAGUUCCAGAAGUUUUGCAGUCCAUAAUUCUUACAAUUGACAGACUAAUCUGCAAGGAGGAAGUAUUUUCUUGAAAAAUUUUGACAGAAUCAUCAAUUUUUACAGGGUAAGGGUACAAAUAAUUUUAAAGGGAGAAGUUACCAACUUUGAUUUUCAAGUGAGUUAUUCAUGUUAUGGAGUGUUUUCAUUCACCUGUAGCAUUGUGAGGAUGAAGUGAAAAGAUAAAUCUCCCGAGUCUUGUGUAUCUUACUGUCCAUGUGUGAUGGCUCAGGUCUCUAAUUCUAACACUUGGGGAGGCCGAGGCUUGCAGAGCACUUUAGGACAGGAGUUGAAGACCAGGC